GAGGGCGGCGGGCUGCCGCGCAAGGGUGGCGCGCGCGCGGUGAGUGUGCGAGUGUCGGCGGCGCCGGAUCCUCUACGUGGGGCCCGGGCUCUGCGGGCGGGAGGCGGGAGCUGGCAGCCCCAGGCGGUAGCGCUUCGUCCUGCGGCCUGGGUGUGUCAGGAGUCGCUGCGGUCGGGGCGCCCUUGCCUCAGGAGACUUAGAUCCCCGCUGAUCCGCCCGUCCCGCCGCAGUGGUCUGAGCCGCAGCCCUUUCCCGUGCCGCCCGCGGGUCCCGUUCCUCCCGUGUCUCCAUGCCGCAGCCAGCGUGGCCGCGGCUACCUUGCCCUCGCCCCCGCUCCGCUUCUGCCGCUCCCGGCACUGCCUUACUCCUUUGGGUUGCAUCUCUUUCCUGGCUUUUCACCCUUGCUGAUUCUGUAAGGGAUAGUGCAGCCAGCGGACGUCCCAGGCCAAAUGUUUUUUGAUAGGCAGUCGAGGACUUUCCCGAGGGCGGUGGUUGAGGGCGAGGCUGCCAGCCUCCGAAGAGCAGCGGCACGCCAGGGAGCCGGGCGGGGAGGGGAGUGCUGCCACCGAGGUCGGGAGCAGGGUCCUCGGCCUCACUAGGUCCUGUGUGGCCGAUACUUCCUGCCCACGACCGCCCCCCGGAUUUCCAUUUGCUAAUACCGGUCCGCAGCCUUCUUUCCUGAAAGUUGCAUAAAGUUGGAAGCUCUUCAACUUGCCUCCCCGACUCCUGAAAUCCCGAAUACACCUCUGAAAAGGAGUGUACUCACAAGUAUUCUCAUUUUUCAAUGAGAGUCAGUCAGUGAGUCAUUAAGGAAGUUUUCCUUGUUCCUGGUCAACAAAGAAAUGUGGAGUGUCUUGGCUGAAUCCUCAUACAGACAAGAUCAUUAUGGUGCUGUUAGGUAGGACUUGUAUCCAGAUGUAAGGUUGAAAAAGUGAUAUAAUAAAGGAACCAAGGAGAAAAUUCAGAAGGAAAGAAAAAAUUGCCUCUGCAGGUGUGCGAGCAGGAUUGCUUCUGCAACAAAAGCCUCCACCCAGCCACAUCUUGGGAAAAGAAUGGCCACUUCUUGGGGCACAGUCUUUUUCAUGCUGGUGGUAUCCUGUGUUUGCAGCGCUGUCUCCCACAGGAACCAGCAGACUUGGUUUGAGGGUAUCUUCCUGUCUUCCAUGUGCCCCAUCAAUGUCAGCGCCAGCACCUUGUAUGGAAUUAUGUUUGAUGCAGGGAGCACUGGAACUCGAAUUCAUGUUUACACCUUUGUGCAGAAAAUGCCAGGACAGCUUCCAAUUCUAGAAGGGGAAGUUUUUGAUUCUGUGAAGCCAGGACUUUCUGCUUUUGUAGAUCAACCUAAGCAGGGUGCUGAGACCGUUCAAGGGCUCUUAGAGGUGGCCAAAGACUCAAUCCCCCGAAGUCACUGGAAAAAGACCCCAGUGGUCCUAAAGGCAACAGCAGGACUACGCUUACUGCCAGAACACAAAGCCAAGGCUCUGCUCUUUGAGGUAAAGGAGAUCUUCAGGAAGUCACCUUUCCUGGUACCAAAGGGCAGUGUUAGCAUCAUGGAUGGAUCCGACGAAGGCAUAUUAGCUUGGGUUACUGUGAAUUUUCUGACAGGUCAGCUGCAUGGCCACAGACAGGAGACUGUGGGGACCUUGGACCUAGGGGGAGCCUCCACCCAAAUCACGUUCCUGCCCCAGUUUGAGAAAACUCUGGAACAAACUCCUAGGGGCUACCUCACUUCCUUUGAGAUGUUUAACAGCACUUAUAAGCUCUAUACACAUAGUUACCUGGGAUUUGGAUUGAAAGCUGCAAGACUAGCAACCCUGGGAGCCCUGGAGACAGAAGGGACUGAUGGGCACACUUUCCGGAGUGCCUGUUUACCGAGAUGGUUGGAAGCAGAGUGGAUCUUUGGGGGUGUGAAAUACCAGUAUGGUGGCAACCAAGAAGGGGAGGUGGGCUUUGAGCCCUGCUAUGCCGAAGUGCUGAGGGUGGUACGAGGAAAACUUCACCAGCCAGAGGAGGUCCAGAGAGGUUCCUUCUAUGCUUUCUCUUACUAUUAUGACCGAGCUGUUGACACAGACAUGAUUGAUUAUGAAAAGGGGGGUAUUUUAAAAGUUGAAGAUUUUGAAAGAAAAGCCAGGGAAGUGUGUGAUAACUUGGAAAACUUCACCUCAGGCAGUCCUUUCCUGUGCAUGGAUCUCAGCUACAUCACAGCCCUGUUAAAGGAUGGCUUUGGCUUUGCAGACAGCACAGUCUUACAGCUCACAAAGAAAGUGAACAACAUAGAGACGGGCUGGGCCUUGGGGGCCACCUUUCACCUGUUGCAGUCUCUGGGCAUCUCCCAUUGAGGCCACGUACUUCCUUGGAGACCUGCAUUUGCCAACACCUUUUUAAGGGGAGGAGAGAGCACUUAGUUUCUGAACUAGUCUGGGGACAUCCUGGACUUGAGCCUAGAGAUUUAGGUUUAAUUAAUUUUACACAUCUAAUGUGAACUGCUGCCUAACCACUCAAGAGUACACAGCUGGCACCAGAGCAUCACAGAGAGCCCUGUGAGCCAAAAAGUAUAGUUUUGGAACUUAACCUUGGAGUGAGAGCCCAGGGACAGGUCCCUGGAAACCAAAGAAAAAUCGCAUUUCAACCCUUUGAGUGCCUCAUUCCACUGAAUAUUUAAAUUUUCCUCUUAAAUGGUAAACUGACUUAUUGCAAUCCCAAGACCCAUCAAUAUCAGUAUUUUUUUCCUCCCUAUACAGUGCCCUGCCCACCCUUAUCUGCACCCACCUCCCCUGAAAAAGAGAGAAAAAAAAAAACCUGGUUUUGCUUUCCAUGUAUAAUUCAACAACGCAAAAUGGGACCAUGUCAGAAUCUGUAUGAUCCUAUUCUGUGUUAGCUCCAAUCAGCCAGCUGAGAGCCAUCCUAAAUAUUAAUAGGAUGAGAGAGUAACUCCUAACUGUGCAUAAAUUACAGCCUUAAGAAAGAAGGCCACCCGGUCUCUGGGGACAUGUUUUGGGAGGGUGUGGCUGCCUCAUAUAGCCUACCUUUGCUUUAAUCAGCAUUUUAUCAGUCAACUCUGGGAUUAAUGAACAUAUCCGACUUUAUGGGUAUGUGUAUAUUCAGUGCCAGUACCACCUCCCAGGCUAAUGUGUUAACAGUGUUUUCUAUGAUUCUAAACUUGUUUUCUUUGUAUUUCUAAGAAAUACAACUAGGCCCUAACUUUUGGUCUGUGGUCAGAGGUCAGUGUCUGUGCUAUUCCAGGAUCUAUUAUUUCAGUUUGCCCUUUUAUUCUCUCCGUUUGUAACAGUACCUUCCUGUCCUGGUCCCUGAUCACUUUAGCUAAUAUCCUUUGAAUUAUUUAUCUAGUUCAGAGUUUCCAAUACCGUUCCUGACAAAACCCCACUUGGAUUUGGUUGGCUCUCUCAGCCCACAUCAGUACAGUGGACCAACAUUUCCAGGGAGAACCAUAUUUAAUGUCCCUCAUGCUCUCUUUUUGAAUCCAAGUGCUCAGAGCUCUUGACUGUGAAUUAUUUACCCCAAAUUCAUUAUCUUGCACUUUUUUUUGAGAUGGAGUCUUGCUCUGUUGCUCAGGCUAGAGUGGAGUGGCGCAAUCUCAGCUCACUGCAACCUCCGCCCCCAGGUUCAAGCGAUUCUUGUUCUCAGCCUCCUGAAGAGCUGGGAUUACAGGUGCCCACCACCAUUCCUGGCUAAUUUUUGUAUUUGUAGUAGAGAUGGGGUUUCACCAUGUUGGCCAGGCUGGUUUCCAACUCCUGAUCUCAAUUGAUCCACCCGCUUCCCAAAGUGCUGGGAUUACAGGCAUGAGACACCGCGCCUGGCCUUAUCUUGCACUUUCAACAUAAUCAUCCCUGCUUCUCAUCUGCCCUGCAGUGCUCUUGGACCUGGAAGAUCUCCCUGUGGUCUGGCCCCUUUGCCUUGGUUGUUAACCUCCAGCUUCUUUGCAGGAGUGUAUUUCCCCAAAACUUGUGGCUUUCACAGUAGACUCCGUUUCCAUCCUCUCUCUCACAAAGGAUGUUAAGUAUGCCUGGCCCUCACACAGUCCAUGGGAAACCUUAUUUUUAACAUUACUCCAUUGAGUCAAUAAAUAUUUACCAUCUGCUGUGUGCAAGUUACUAGGCAAAUUUCUGUAUCCUUGUCCCUAAAAUUCUUGUCUUUAAAUUCAUUGUGGAAUUUCUUUAGACUUCACACUGACUUUUAUUACUAAGGUCACCUUUAUACCAACUGCCUUCCUCAAAAUGCUUAUAAUGAAAUAACAGAAUCUUGAGUUGGAAACAGCCCAAAGAAAUAAUCCAAUGUUGUACUCAGUGCAGAAUUCCCUAGAAUUUCUAACAGGUUGUCAUUCAGCUUCUGCUAAGCCAUGUUCAAACAGCUUAUUCCAUUUGGAACUGCACUGAUAUUAAAAAAAAUUCCUUAUAUUGAGCUGAAAUCUACCUAUCUUCUAAGUGGUCUUAGUUCUGCUCUAAUCUCUCCUUCCAAAAUCUUUGGAUCUUUUGAAAAAAGUUCCUCCCAAGUUCUUUUAUAAGUGACAUGACUUUUAGACCCCUUCCCAUCUUUGUCAACAAAAGUAGGGUGCCAGACCAGUCACAGAACACUAAAUGUCAUCCAUGUUUCCUUCAGUAGAAACCAGCAGUUUUAAAAGAGGUAAGCUGUGUUCACUAAAGACUGUUCCAGCUUGACAAAUGCAGAGAUAUAAGUCUCUGGUCUUUAAUCACUGUGGGGGCCAUUUUGUAAAACACACAUACUGUCCAGCAGACUCCUUUGGUCAUCCCAAAUACCUCUGAACUCCAGGGAAGAUGCAUUCUAACUCCACGAACUUACCUAUUUUGUUAACCUUGAUUAGACCUUCUGGAGAAGUAACCAAUUUGUCCAUCUUAGGAGCAAUUUGGAAUGAGAGUUUUUAUUUUUUUCUGUAACGCCCAUCCUGCCUGCAGUAGACCCUUUGGGCUUAAGAGGUCCUACAGAUUCUAAUAGUUUCCUCUUUGUAGAUGUGUUAACAUAUUUAAAAUACUUAGGACAUGGCCUGGUACGUGACAGAUGGUGUUUAACAUCAUUGUCAUAUGAAGAACACUCUCUGUGGGCCAAUGGAGGUGUGCCUUAAAAUUCUUCAUCUUGCCUGAUUUUGUUUGCAUAACUUCUGGAGAGUCUGUGUCCUCCUCAUCUAGGCCACCUUUCCAUUUUUUGUGAAAGAUGACCUUGUCCCUGCAGUCUCCGCCAGGAGUCACACAGCUUUUCACAGCAGCUGCCAUCUUUAAUUCUUUUUCCUGAGAUUCCAGCAAGGUUGUGACAUUGUCACUUUUUUGUUCUAGACUCUUUUAAAUUUUCUGCAUUUGCCUGAAAAGCACCCCUGUAAGAAUAGAUUUCUCAUGGCUCUAAAAAUUAUUCCCAAGAAUACCUUACUUGGUUCAAAAGCAGACUGUUUCUCUUCAUUUCAUCUCAAAUCAGACUUCUGGGCAAGAUGUUCUUUAGAGUAAGCAAACCUACAACCUAAAAAUCUCUUCAAGAGGCAUCUCUGGUCUUGUGACGAGACCUCUUCAAAAACCCACAGUAAAACUCCCCUCCCUCCAGUUGGCCACCAGUCUGCCACCAAACAUGAACAAAUUCUGCUGCUAAUCGGUUUCCCUUGUGAUCUGGUUCCUGAGGUCUUCGGAUCUGUGCAAUGAAUUAUUUAUUGUUUUAUUAAACCGACAGUGGUGUCCCAGAGAGGAACCAUAAAUAAAAUGGAAAUCUGGUGCUGUGAUAAAGUAAUAACUAGCAUUAAUGAGACCUGGUUUUCCUUUCAGAAAGUCCAGUAUACCUGUAACAAAGGUUAAAGCAAUUUAUAUUUAAUUUGCAUUCUGAUGUUAACAUUUAAACAGCAAUUCUAACAAAAAUGCAUCGAGUCUAAUUCUUACCUCUAUCAAAAAACAACUGUAUAAAUUUAUGACCAACAUUAAAACAAAAACAAAAUGUAAAUUUUCUCUUUAGAAAUGAUUAACUGGAAAUGAGUGAGACAGCACCUUGUGGGUUUUUUAGUAAUAAAAAGCUCUUUUCAACCAAA